GUCGCGCUCCCCCGGGAUGGCCCGCGCGCCUCGGCGCUGCCUCUCGGAGCUCACGGCGGAGCGGCGGCGGCCGCGCUCGAGGGGCGCGCGGCUGCAGCGGCGGCGGCGCCGCGCGUGAGGGGCCGCCUAAGGCCGAGCGGGCGCGGCGAGCGGCCGGGCGAGCGCAGCCAACAUGUCGGAUACCAAGGUAAAAGUUGCCGUCCGGGUCCGGCCCAUGAACCGACGAGAACUGGAACUGAACACCAAGUGCGUGGUGGAGAUGGAAGGGAAUCAAACGGUCCUGCACCCUCCUCCUUCUAACACCAAACAGGGAGAAAGGAAACCUCCCAAGGUAUUUGCCUUUGAUUAUUGCUUUUGGUCCAUGGAUGAAUCUAACACUACAAAAUACGCUGGUCAAGAAGUGGUUUUCAAGUGCCUUGGGGAAGGAAUUCUUGAAAAAGCCUUUCAGGGGUAUAAUGCGUGUAUUUUUGCAUAUGGACAGACAGGUUCGGGAAAAUCCUUUUCCAUGAUGGGCCAUGCUGAGCAGCUGGGCCUUAUUCCAAGGCUCUGCUGUGCUUUAUUUAAAAGGAUCUCUUUGGAGCAAAAUGAGUCACAGACCUUUAAAGUUGAAGUGUCCUAUAUGGAAAUUUAUAAUGAGAAAGUUCGGGAUCUUUUAGACCCCAAAGGGAGUAGACAGUCUCUUAAAGUUCGAGAACAUAAAGUUUUGGGACCAUAUGUAGAUGGUUUAUCUCAACUAGCUGUCACUAGUUUUGAGGAUAUUGAGUCAUUGAUGUCUGAGGGAAAUAAGUCUCGAACGGUAGCUGCUACCAACAUGAACGAAGAAAGCAGCCGCUCCCAUGCUGUGUUCAACAUCAUAAUCACACAGACACUUUAUGACCUGCAGUCUGGGAAUUCCGGGGAGAAAGUCAGUAAGGUCAGCUUGGUAGACCUGGCGGGUAGCGAAAGAGUAUCUAAAACAGGAGCUGCAGGAGAGCGACUGAAAGAAGGCAGCAACAUUAACAAAUCGCUUACAACCUUGGGGUUGGUUAUAUCAUCACUGGCUGACCAGGCAGCUGGCAAGGGUAAAAGCAAAUUUGUGCCUUAUCGAGAUUCAGUCCUCACUUGGCUGCUUAAGGACAACUUGGGGGGCAACAGCCAAACCUCUAUGAUAGCCACAAUCAGCCCAGCCGCAGACAACUAUGAAGAGACCCUCUCCACAUUAAGAUAUGCAGACCGAGCCAAAAGGAUUGUGAACCAUGCUGUUGUGAAUGAGGACCCCAACGCAAAAGUGAUCCGAGAACUGCGGGAGGAAGUCGAGAAACUGAGAGAGCAGCUCUCUCAGGCAGAGGCCAUGAAGGCCCCUGAACUGAAGGAGAAGCUCGAAGAGUCUGAAAAGCUGAUAAAAGAACUAACAGUGACUUGGGAAGAGAAGCUGAGAAAAACAGAAGAGAUAGCACAGGAAAGACAACGACAACUUGAAAGCAUGGGGAUUUCCCUGGAGAUGUCCGGUAUCAAGGUGGGGGAUGACAAAUGCUACUUAGUCAAUCUGAAUGCAGACCCUGCUCUUAACGAACUUCUGGUUUAUUAUUUAAAGGAUCACACCAGGGUGGGUGCAGAUACCUCUCAAGAUAUCCAGCUUUUUGGCAUAGGAAUUCAGCCUCAGCACUGUGAGAUUGACAUUGCAUCUGAUGGAGACGUCACUCUCACUCCAAAAGAAAAUGCAAGGUCCUGUGUGAACGGCACCCUUGUGUGCAGUACCACCCAGCUGUGGCAUGGUGACCGAAUCCUAUGGGGAAAUAAUCACUUUUUUAGAAUAAACUUACCUAAGAGGAAACGUCGAGAUUGGUUGAAAGACUUUGAAAAAGAAACGGGCCCGCCAGAGCAUGACCUGGAUGCAGCCAGUGAGGCUUCCUCUGAACCAGACUAUAACUAUGAAUUUGCACAGAUGGAAGUUAUCAUGAAAACCCUGAAUAGUAAUGACCCAGUUCAAAAUGUGGUUCAGGUCCUGGAGAAACAAUACCUAGAAGAAAAGAGAAGUGCCCUAGAGGAGCAGCGGCUCAUGUAUGAGCGGGAACUGGAGCAACUCCGCCAGCAGCUCUCCCCCGACAGGCAGCCACAGAGUAGCGGCCCUGACCGCCUGGCCUACAGCAGCCAGACAGCGCAGCAGAAGGUGACCCAGUGGGCAGAAGAGAGGGAUGAACUCUUCCGACAAAGCCUGGCAAAACUGCGAGAGCAGCUGGUUAAAGCUAAUACCUUGGUGAGGGAAGCAAACUUCCUGGCUGAGGAAAUGAGCAAACUCACCGAUUACCAAGUGACUCUUCAGAUCCCUGCUGCAAACCUCAGUGCCAAUAGGAAGAGAGGUGCAAUAGUGAGUGAACCAGCUAUCCAAGUGAGGAGGAAAGGAAAGAGCACCCAAGUGUGGACCAUUGAGAAGCUGGAGAAUAAAUUAAUUGACAUGAGAGACCUUUACCAAGAAUGGAAGGAAAAAGUUCCUGAGGCAAAGAGACUCUACGGAAAACGAGGUGACCCUUUCUAUGAAGCCCAAGAAAAUCACAACCUCAUCGGGGUGGCGAAUGUAUUCUUGGAAUGCCUCUUCUGUGAUGUGAAACUUCAGUAUGCAGUCCCUAUCAUCAGCCAGCAGGGGGAGGUUGCAGGGCGUCUCCACGUGGAAGUGAUGCGUGUUACAGGAGCUGUUCCAGAGCGUGUGGUGGAGGAUGACUCUUCGGAGAAUUCCAGUGAAAGUGGGAGCCUUGAAGUCGUAGACAGCAGCGGGGAAAUCAUUCACCGAGUCAAAAAGCUGACAUGUCGGGUAAAAAUUAAAGAAGCAACGGGGCUGCCCUUAAACCUCUCAAAUUUUGUCUUCUGUCAAUACACAUUCUGGGACCAGUGUGAGUCUACGGUGGCUGCCCCGGUGGUGGACCCCGAGGUGCCUUCACCACAGUCCAAGGAUGCCCAGUACACAGUGACCUUCUCCCACUGUAAGGACUAUGUGGUGAAUGUAACAGAAGAAUUUCUGGAGUUCAUUUCAGAUGGAGCACUGGCCAUUGAAGUAUGGGGCCACCGGUGUGCUGGAAAUGGCAGCUCCAUCUGGGAGGUCGAUUCUCUUCAUGCUAAGACAAGAACACUGCAUGACAGGUGGAAUGAAGUAACGCGAAGAAUAGAAAUGUGGAUCUCCAUAUUAGAAUUGAAUGAGUUAGGAGAGUAUGCUGCAGUGGAACUUCAUCAGGCAAAAGAUGUCAACACAGGAGGCAUCUUUCAACUUAGACAGGGUCAUUCCCGUAGAGUACAAGUCACGGUGAAACCUGUGCAGCAUUCAGGGACACUGCCACUUAUGGUUGAAGCCAUCCUGUCAGUAUCCAUCGGCUGUGUAACUGCCAGGUCCACCAAACUCCAAAGAGGGCUGGACAGUUACCAGGAAGAAGACUUAAACUGCGUAAGGGAGAGGUGGUCAGAUGCACUCAUUAAACGACGAGAAUACCUGGAUGAACAGAUAAAAAAAGUCAGCAAUAAAACAGAGAAAACAGAGGACGAUGUGGAGCGGGAAGCCCAGCUUGUGGAGCAGUGGGUAGGGCUGACUGAGGAAAGGAAUGCUGUGCUGGUGCCAGCCCCAGGCAGUGGGAUUCCUGGGGCACCUGCCGACUGGAUCCCACCUCCUGGAAUGGAAACCCACAUACCAGUUCUCUUCCUCGAUUUGAAUGCGGAUGACCUCAGUGCCAAUGAGCAGCUUGUUGGCCCCCAUGCAUCCGGCGUGAACUCCAUCCUGCCCAAGGAGCAUGGCAGCCAGUUUUUCUACCUGCCCAUCAUAAAGCACAGUGAUGAUGAGGUUUCAGCCACAGCCUCUUGGGAUUCCUCGGUGCAUGAUUCUGUUCACUUGAAUAGGGUCACACCACAGAAUGAAAGGAUUUACCUAAUUGUGAAAACCACAGUUCAACUCAGCCACCCUGCUGCUAUGGAGUUAGUAUUACGAAAACGAAUUGCAGCCAAUAUUUACAACAAACAGAGUUUCACGCAGAGUUUGAAGAGGAGAAUAUCCCUGAAAAAUAUAUUUUAUUCCUGUGGUGUAACCUAUGAAAUAGUAUCCAAUAUACCAAAGGCAACUGAGGAGAUAGAGGACCGGGAAACGCUGGCUCUCCUGGCAGCAAGGAGUGAAAACGAAGGCACAUCAGAUGGGGAGACGUACAUUGAGAAGUACACUCGAGGCGUGCUGCAGGUGGAAAACAUUCUGAGUCUUGAACGGCUCCGGCAGGCCGUCACAGUCAAAGAAGCACUUUCCACCAAAGCCCGGCACAUUCGGAGGAGCCUCAGUACACCAAAUGUUCAUAAUGUCUCUUCCAGCCGACCGGACCUUUCUGGCUUUGAUGAAGAUGACAAGGGUUGGCCAGAGAACCAGUUGGACAUGUCUGACUAUAGCUCCAGUUACCAAGAUGUAGCAUGUUAUGGAACUUUACCCAGGGAUUCUCCUCGAAGGAAUAAAGAAGGUUGUACAUCAGAGACUCCUCAUGCCUUAACCGUCAGCCCUUUUAAAGCAUUCUCUCCUCAGCCACCAAAGUUUUUCAAGCCCCUAAUGCCUGUAAAAGAGGAGCAUAAGAAAAGGAUAGCCCUGGAAGCAAGGCCUCUUCUAAGCCAGGAGGACUCUGAGGAGGAAGAAAAUGAGCUGGAAGCUAUUAACAGGAAGCUAAUAAGUUCACAGCCUUAUGUACCUGUGGAGUUUGCUGACUUCAGUGUUUACAAUGCCAGCUUGGAGAACAGGGAAUGGUUUUCCUCUAAAGUAGAUCUGUCAAACUCACGGGUCUUGGAGAAAGAAGUGUCCCGUAGCCCUACCACCAGCAGUAUUACCAGUGGCUACUUUUCCCACAGUGCCUCCAAUGCCACCCUGUCUGACAUGGUGGUCCCUUCUAGUGACAGCUCAGACCAGCUGGCCAUUCAGACGAAGGAUGCAGACUCCACCGAGCACUCCACACCAUCGCUUGUGCAUGAUUUCAGGCCGUCCUCAAACAAAGAGUUGACAGAAGUCGAAAAAGGCUUGGUAAAGGACAAGAUAAUUGUGGUGCCACUCAAGGAAAACAGUGCCUUAGCCAAAGGGAGCCCAUCAUCCCAGAGCAUCCCUGAGAAAAACUCCAAAUCACUGUGCAGGACUGGCUCAUGUUCAGAACUAGAUGCCUGCCCCAGCAAAAUUAGCCAGCCAGCCAGGGGAUUCUGCCCCAGGGAGGUGACGGUAGAACACACCACCAACAUCCUUGAAGACCAUUCUUUCACAGAAUUUAUGGGAGUGUCAGAGGGAAAAGAUUUUGAUGGUUUGACAGAUUCUUCUGCUGGAGAGCUUUCCAGUAGGAGGAGUCUACCAAAUAAAACAGGCGGCAAGACUGUCUCCGAUGGGCUCCACCACCCCAGCCAGCUGCAUUCCAAGUUAGAGAAUGACCAGGGAGGCACAACCUCACGGUGAGAGCAGCAAGCACCCCUCCUCAGGCCACAGCUUGGCGUCUUUGUUCGCCUGGUCACCUUGGGCAAGCACCAGCCCCAUCUCUAAAACAUGCUGCCGCCUGGCUGGACCUCAGACCAGAAGCUGGAGAAUCCACACCGUGCACUUCCUGGGCCACCUCCUUUCCCCUCCCCAGUGGGAGAAGCGGCACUUUGUCACUUGGGUGAAUCAACAGCCUCUGCUUUUUCCAGAAAGCAAGAGAACUGAAAAUCCUGGAUUAACUAAGUGACAGUAUUUUUUUUUGCACUUACUACACACCUCCACUGUAUAGAAACCUCUACAGAUUCCAACAGACUUUAUUCUUGUACAAUUUUAAUCAGUUCUUACUGUAGAAUCUGGAGUCAAUGCUCUAAUCUGUUUUUUAUAAAUAAUAUAUAUUAUGUAUAUGAAAUGUGUAUCUAUAGUAUGUCUGGAGACAGACAAGGCUGCACACUAAAAUGCAGAUAAAGGUGAUUUGUAGAAAAUCAUAAGGUACUGGACUUCGUUACAAAGCAACUUGGGCGAUCUCUUAUACAUGAGCAGAUGAAAAAUAUUUUAUUGCCUAAGAAUGAGCUUGCAAAUCCCUCUUUGCAGAAAAGGUUAUAGAAUGCUGUUCUUUAUAACCAAAGAACUUACAUAAGACAACAUUUUUGCUGUCCACUCUUUUGUGUGAACAUGUAUGUUUGACUGCAAGUUUGGUGCCAUAAUUCCCUUGGCUACCAAGCCACGUGCUGCCAUUCUCUGUCCUUUGUUUCAUAAGCACACUGAGAAAUCUCACAGCUAUAUUCUUUGGUCUUCCACCUGCCCCUCCACCUGCUGACUUGACAUUGUAUUAUAACUGUUGACAAUGACUGGGGUCCUGACUCCACAGUUGCCUGGACCGUGGCUCAGCCCAGCUGGGCAGGUGGAAUGAAGAGAGCCGUAUUACUGUAAGAAAACACAAGGACAGCCAGGAGUAGUGGUGGGGUGGGUGGGGUGGGAGGUGUUGAUUUUUGUGUGUUUCUGUGUGUGUGGUUUUGUUUUGGAUUGGUAGGUUUCACUGUGGCGUGGUUUUGCUGUUGUUAUUUUGCUUGAUUCUGGAAAAUGCUGAGGAGAUGGACUGAGCUAUGAAGUUCAAUGGUUCACCCUUUACCAUGUUUGCAGGAGAUGAUCGAAUACAGAUGACCCUGCUGUCGUGUCUUCAUUUGUAAAAUUCUCCUACAAAUGGAGACAUUGAAGGAUUAUGUGUAUGGAAAUUUUUACAAAAUUCCUUUCUGUACCUAUUCUGUAGAUGCCUGUAUAAUCGGUCUGGAUGUACAGCUAUAAAUGUGUUGUGAGAGCAAGAGAGAGAGAAUGGGUAGAGCCUGCUGUACCUUUUUUCUUUUAAAUUCUUCGAGUUGGUAAAUGAGUAAGAUAUUGGAAACCUUAAUGAAAAGCUGCUGUUCAUGAUUUGUGUGUAUAGUGAGCUGACUGUAGUAUUUUACUAUUGUCUGUUAAAAAAAGAAAAACUGUAAUUUAUAUCCCCUUUGAACUUUAUUGUGUUUAAUUGGUACACAUUUCUGUGUGUGUGUGUGUGUAUGUGUUUUAGAAUACAAACUGUGUAAUUCAGAUUUUAAAACACUAAUCAUUUGUCUUUAAUAACCCUGCCUUUAGUUUCAAAUCUAACUUACCAUAUUUCUAUGUGUGCAUGUCUCUGCAGUGUUAAAAAUAAUAAUAUCAGCAUUUAUUAGGGGUCAA